GGAGGCGGUGGUGUCCCGGCUGCGGGGUAGGAGUCCGCGGCAGCCUCCGGGUAAGCCAAGCGCCGCGCAGUGCUGAGUUCCCGCACGCCGCAGAGCCAUGGAGAUCGGCACCGAGAUCAGCCGCAAGAUCCGGAGUGCCAUUAAGGGGAAAUUACAAGAAUUAGGAGCUUAUGUUGUAUUUGAAAUACCUGUGGAAUGAAGAGAAAAAAAUUAAAGCUAAGCCAUCUUGUCCAAUGUAAUUCCAGUAGAGCUCUGCGACUCUAAAGCUUAGAGCUACAUCUAUAUUUUCAAGCACAUCAACUUUAAGAAGAAAGUUUUGAGGAAACAAAGUUUUGAUCUACCUUUCCUUUUAAAUAGAUGAAGAACUUCCUGAUUACAUUAUGGUGAUGGUGGCCAACAAGAAAAGUCAGGACCAAAUGACAGAGGAUCUGUCCCUGUUUCUAGGGAACAACACAAUUCGAUUCACCGUAUGGCUUCAUGGUGUAUUAGAUAAACUUCGCUCUGUUACAACUGAACCCUCUAGUCUGAAGUCUUCUGAUACCAACAUCUUUGAUAGUAACGUGCCUUCAAACAAGAGCAAUUUCAGUCGGGGAGAUGAGAGGAGGCAUGAAGCUGCAGUGCCACCACUUGCCAUUCCUAGCGCGAGACCUGAAAAAAGAGAUUCCAGAGUUUCUACAAGUUCGCAGGAGUCAAAAACCACAAAUGUCAGACAGACUUACGAUGAUGGAGCUGCAACCCGACUAAUGUCAACAGUGAAACCUUUGAGGGAGCCAGCACCCUCUGAAGAUGUGAUUGAUAUUAAGCCAGAACCAGAUGAUCUCAUUGACGAAGACCUCAACUUUGUGCAGGAGAAUCCCUUAUCUCAGAAAAAACCUACAGUGACACUUACAUAUGGUUCUUCUCGCCCUUCUAUUGAAAUUUAUCGACCACCUGCAAGUAGAAAUGCAGAUAGUGGUGUUCAUUUAAACAGGUUGCAAUUUCAACAGCAGCAGAAUAGUAUUCAUGCUGCCAAGCAGCUUGAUAUGCAGAGUAGUUGGGUAUAUGAAACAGGACGUUUGUGUGAACCAGAGGUGCUUAACAGCUUAGAAGAAACGUAUAGUCCGUUCUUUAGAAACAACUCGGAGAAAAUGAGUAUGGAGGAUGAAAACUUUCGGAAGAGAAAGUUGCCUGUGGUAAGUUCAGUUGUUAAAGUAAAAAAAUUCAAUCAUGAUGGAGAAGAGGAGGAAGAAGAUGAUGAUUACGGGUCUCGAACAGGAAGCAUCUCCAGCAGUGUGUCUGUGCCUGCAAAGCCUGAAAGGAGACCUUCUCUUCCACCUUCUAAACAAGCUAACAAGAAUCUGAUUUUGAAGGCUAUAUCUGAAGCUCAAGAAUCCGUAACAAAAACAACUAACUACUCUACAGUUCCACAGAAACAGACACUUCCAGUUGCUCCCAGAACUCGAACUUCUCAAGAAGAAUUGCUAGCAGAAGUGGUCCAGGGACAAAGUAGGACCCCCAGAAUAAGUCCCCCCAUUAAAGAAGAGGAAACAAAAGGAGAUUCUGUAGAAAAAAAUCAAGGAACUCAACAGAGGCAAUUAUUAUCCCGACUGCAAAUCGACCCAGUAAUGGCAGAAACUCUGCAGAUGAGUCAAGAUUACUAUGACAUGGAAUCCAUGGUCCAUGCAGACACAAGAUCAUUUAUUCUGAAGAAGCCAAAGCUGUCUGAGGAAGUAGUAGUGGCACCAAACCAAGAGUCGGGGAUGAAGACUGCAGAUUCCCUUCGGGUACUUUCAGGACACCUUAUGCAGACACGAGAUCUUGUACAACCAGAUAAACCUGCAAGUCCCAAGUUUAUAGUGACGCUGGAUGGUGUCCCCAGCCCCCCAGGAUACAUGUCAGAUCAAGAGGAGGACAUGUGCUUUGAAGGAAUGAAACCCGUAAACCAAACUGCAGCCUCAAACAAGGGACUCAGAGGUCUCCUCCACCCACAGCAGUUGCACUUGCUGAGCAGGCAGCUUGAGGACCCAAAUGGUAGCUUUUCUAACGCUGAGAUGAGUGAACUGAGUGUGGCACAGAAACCAGAAAAACUUUUGGAGCGCUGCAAGUACUGGCCUGCUUGUAAAAAUGGGGAUGAGUGUGCCUACCAUCACCCCAUCUCACCCUGCAAAGCCUUCCCCAAUUGUAAAUUUGCUGAAAAAUGUUUGUUUGUUCACCCAAAUUGUAAAUAUGAUGCAAAGUGUACUAAACCAGAUUGUCCCUUCACUCAUGUGAGUAGAAGAAUUCCAGUACUGUCUCCAAAACCAGCAGUUGCACCACCAGCACCACCUUCCAGUAGUCAGCUCUGCCGUUACUUCCCUGCUUGUAAGAAGAUGGAAUGUCCCUUCUAUCAUCCAAAACAUUGUAGGUUUAACACUCAAUGUACAAGACCGGACUGCACAUUCUACCAUCCCACCAUUAAUGUCCCACCACGACAUGCCUUGAAAUGGAUUCGACCUCAAACCAGCGAAUAGCACCCAGUCCUGCCUGGCAGAAGAUCAUGCAGUUUGGAAGUUUUCAUGUACUGAUGAAAGAUACUCUACAGAACUUGUCAAAUCUUUGAAACUUGGAAUAUAUUGCUUUCAUAAUAUGAAGUUUUAUUGCCUAUCUAUCUGAAGUGUCUAAUUUUUCAAGUUUGUAAGUUUAUUAUGUGGUUUUAACAUUGGGUGUUUUUGUUUUGUUUUUACUAUGAAAAGACAGCUUAAGGAAGAGCUAAAUUCUGUUAAAAUAUUUGGGGCAUGUUUGUGCACUGCUGUUGUGAGGAUCAGCAUAUGAAAUUGACAUCAUGGUUAGUCAUGGUACUGCAGCUUAGGGGGCUACACGGUUGCUGUGUGAGUGGAGAGAUGCAGUGAGGCAGUUGUCAUUAUUCUAAAAAUUGUACUACUUUCACUUUUCCCAAAGAUUAUAUAAUGUUCAUAAUCCACCAUGAAAACAGCAUUGGCCAAAGGUACUGAGGCUGCUUAAAAUAUUCAAUUCUGCUUUUUAAUUUUUAAGUGAAUUUAGUUUGAAAAGCAUGAUUAUACAGGCCUCUCAGGCUGAGUGCUACUUUGGUAAAGUUCCCAGUUUUCCUGCCUUCUGUGACAGGAUGAAUGAGGUGGGUAUGGACAGUGGAGGCAGCUGGAAUGGCAAGUGCAGAAAAUAGGAACAGUUCUAUACAGUGCUCUCAUUUACUAAUAACAUAAUGCCUUCUAAAUAAUUUUUUUGGGAAACUACAUUAUCACAAAAUUAUACAAAUUUUUUUACAAGUAUUUACAUACUGUAUCUGAAAACAGACUUUAAAGUCACAAGAUUAUAAAUGUACAUAUAUAUUCUCACAUUCUGAAAAAUAACAUUCUCAGAAUCCACAGAAAAUAUACUUAGUUACUACUGAAGAUAAUUUUUGAAAUGUAAAAAUUAGAUUUAAAUAGUAUAUUUUAAAUGACAGAACUAUAAUUACAGAGAUCAGAUCAGAUAGGUAAACUGCAAGAUAGAUAGGAUGAAACUUUUGGCCUACUGUAUUACUUACAGAGUUUUUUUGUGUGUGGUUUUUAAAACUGUUAAGGCAAGAAGUGUCAAAUGCUUUAGAGUUAAAUAACAGAUCACUGAUUUCAAAGACUUGGUGUAUAGUGUUAAAAAUUAAAGCUUAAAAGGUGGUUAGAAAAGUGGAUUAAUGCAAAAGGGGUAAUAAAGACUGCAACAUUCUCAGGACCAAAUUAAACUGCUAAAAAAAAAAAAAAAGUUCAUUGACUUGCUUAGUCGUAUACUCAAAUGAUGAUAAACCUACAUGUGCAAAGGCUCACGUUUAAGAUUGUCAAGCCAGCAGUCUACUGUUGUGUUGCCAUUGCUUUUCCAUUGGGAGAAGAAAGAAUUAACCAGUCAUUAAACCAUUUGGUAAGUUGCACUUUGCUGUGCUGAUCCCACAGGAAAGGCUUGAAACACGAGAAGCAGCAAAGACAGAGCACACAAGUGCAUAAGGCUGUUGUCUUCGGCUUGGGUGAAAUGACAGUUCCUCUUCAUUCUAAAGGUUUACUCCAUUGAAUUUAAGGCAUUUGUUCAUUCCAGUGUUGAGAUGCUUUGCAUCUCUGCAGAAGAAAUUUAUUUUAAAUUGUUUAAAUAUCUGGAAAUACUUUUAGCUAUCAUUUAUAAAGAUAGUUUUGUUCUCAGUUUCACUAUAAAUUAUAGAACAAAUGGGAAACAAGGGUUUAAUUUAGUUCAGCCAUUUUACAAGGAAAUAAUAAAAUACUAAAAUCUGAUUGUUUUUUGCUAUUUAAUAGCCACUGCCCAGACACAUAUUUAAGAGUUUAAUCUUUCAGUUGCUAUGGCUUAUGAACAAGCUAAGGUUGACCAUAAAACAUUUGUUGGAUGACGUGGUUUAAAAUGAUCACCACAAAAAGGGACCACAAAAAAAGGAAGGAAAUGAGCAUGGUUGGCGAUUGGAAGCAAGGGUACCAGAGGGCACAGUGUGCUUUGGCAUGCAUUUUAUACAUAAAAUGAAUGGAACAAAAGGUGCCAGAAGUCCCAGGUUACACAAUCAGGAGCUUAGAUACUGCACACAAAAAUAAUUAUCUGGGUUAAAAAAGUAAACAUAGGGCAGAUUCUAUAUGGCCUAUCAUGUUUCUUCACCUUCCCCUCGUUGCUGGCUGAUACAGCGAGGUGGUCAGCUGAUGACUACUUAGUCAAUAUGACCUUUAGUCGUGAAACUGACAGCAGCAGUGAUUAAGGCUGACUUAAUCAGGUUGGCCACUUUGAAGGACAGAAAUGCAGUGGAAACAGUUUUAUUCUAUGUAGUUUACAUGCUUAAGGUUACAGAGUUUCUACCUGCACUGUAAUGGAAAUAUAAUUUCUCUGUAGCCAAAAGCUGGCAAACUUGACCCAGAGGGAAAAUUUAAAACUGCAGCAGGCUCAAAUGUAGAGUAUUUUUCUUUUUAUGGGCAGGUUGUUCAGGGAUUUUUUUCCUCCUUUAAUUUAUUGACUGACUGUAAAUACAUGAGUAGAAACUUAAUAGUCAUGUAUUUCAAAAUUUGGCUUAAUUUAGGAGAAUCCACUGAUGAACAAGUACCAACUUACGUUUCAAGCUUCUUAGCCCCAUAAUCAGUCCUUCAGCCACAGCUAUUUAGAGCUUUAAAACUACCAGGUUCAAUCACUGGUUAUGCUUUCUGUGAUGUAAUUUAGUCAUUUCUAUUUUUAGUAUUAACCAAGUAUUAGACACAGAAAAUAGGUAUUAAGAAUCUUCAUAUAUCCUGUCAGACCAAAUGGGAUUCCAGGAACCUAAAGCGAUCUAUUAUGCUAUAAAGAUAAUUAACACAUUAAAAACUCAUAGGGUCAAUACAGCAUCUUAAACCUCACACUUAGAAAAAUAUAUUUUUAAAUAGCAGUCUACAUAAUUUUCAAUCUUCAGGAAACUACAGAUAGGCUAGACAGCGAAUUCCUGAAUGAUGAGUAGUGAUCUUUGGCAGCAUUUAAAGUGAAAAGAAAUAAGGAUCUAAGAAUUCAGCCCUAAUCCACUAAAAAAAGGAAUUCUAACUGACAAGUUUUUACAAAUGGAGUUGGGCUCAUUCAUUUUGGAAAUAAACCUAUGGAGUGGCACACAUCUAAACAAAUUUUCCCAAUAGAAAAAAGGCUAUAAAAAUUUUAUUCCAAGAGUGAUUAAAUUGUAUAAUGUUGUAUAUGUGAAUUUAACACUUUUGUUUACAUGUUAAACAAAUGUGUAUAUAUUAGACUACAUUAAAUAUGCAAUUCUUUCUUCCAGUUAAAUACUGUUGCUCCCUAAAACCCUUACAUUGUACACCAUUGGGAAUGAUUGUUCAUCAUACUACUUUUCCAUUAGUGAGGCUACAGUUAUGUUUUAAAUGUGCGAUUACAGAGAUGGCAUCUGAACAUAAACUGAUGGCUCGAAAAUGAAAAUGGAAAUGUAGCAGCCAUAUACUGCUAACUUUGGAUCUGUUCCUGAAUUCAAAACUACUAGGAGAAAAGUGUCCUUUAUAAAAAAGGACCUUAUUAAUGCCUAAAAAACAUCAUAUUCUCUAGGAAAGCUUGUGUCUGUUUCCUUAGGGAAAAUGUUUGCCUUUUAAAAACUGUGAUCCUUUAGGAUGAUCAUGACUUUCCCUUUCCUUAUGGAAAUGCAAGAAUAAAAUAUUUCAUUAAACAAUGAACCUUGAAAAUAAAAUAUAAACAUUAAGAAACCAUUUUGCUAAAAAGAUAAUGAAAAUUAUCCAAAUUGGGUUUUUGAGUUCUUCUGUAAAGAGUGCUCUACCCUAAAUUUUCCCAGCAGGUCUGCCGAAAUCACACACUUCCCAAUACAGGGGGACUUGGCCUUUACCAUCAAGUAUUCGAUCCUUCCUUGAAAUGGCAUUAUCUGGCAGUGUAUGGAUUACGGAUUAUACCCAGUGCAUAUAGCAAAUAUUUUGAACAGAUCAGUCUUUCACUAUUUUGAUGAUUCUGGGCAUUUCUCCCUGUUACAGUCUUGGGUUAGCACCACUUGACCAUGCAGGGUUGGGUUUUGGUUUUUCUUCUCUGUAAUUCUGGUCUCAAAGUUAAUUUCUGUAGUCAUCUCAGCAUCUCUCAGUGAGGUGUAUGUACACAUUUCCAGACAAAUAAGCUGCAAUCAGAGAAGAAAAUUGCAGGGAGUUAAUUAUGUUUUUAGAUUUUCAUAACAGUUUAAUAUUUUUCAGUUGUGCUUUCAGGUUACAUGUGUAAUAUUUUUCCUCUUUAACUCCUUUUAUUCUGUAUUUGCAUAAAUAUGAGAUUCUGAAGAGCCAUCUGGUUAUACUACCUUCUACUAAUGUUGACUAGCUGAUUUCAUAAACCAAAGCUGUAGGAGUUGUUGUAUUAAGUCUCUUAACUAGUAACAUAGUCUGCUCUUCAUGGGCUGAGAAAGUUACUAACCUGCAGUCAUCACCUCCAGCACUAACAACAUGUCGAUCACCACUGGUAAAUCGAAUAUUUGUCACAUGGGGCGAAUGACCCAAGAACCUUUUGUGUUUUGCCUAAAAAACAAUGACAGACAAGCUCAGGGCAUUUGGUGCACACAGAAGUCAAAGGCUCUUAUUAGGAACUAUAAUCUCUAUGACAAGAGCUGUGGAGAGAGUAGGGAGUUAGCACCGCAGCCAGUGAUUAGAAUGCUUUUCAGCAUGAGUAGUGGAUCUGCAAAACCAGGCUGUGUGGGCAGUCAGAUGUCUCCAGGUACUCUGACCAUUUUUCUCUAAGGAAAAGCAUUUGAAAUUUGAUAACUGAUUAUAGGUUUGGUGAAAAGCUAAUUACAGCUUUUGUAGGAUGGUUCCAAAGAUGGUAUUACUCGAGGGAGAGGAUUUGUUUCUAAUAGCUUUUAUUUCAAAGUAAAUAGAUUUAGAAAGUUUGGGGAAAAAUUUAGAAAUUAGGACAAAACAUUUUAAAUAUAUGGGGAAAAGUGCUGAUGAUAAGACAUCAAAAUUAGGAGUAAACUGAUAAUAGUAAACAAAACACAAACUUACAAAUUUUUCUGGACAUGGGAAGUCAAAUAACUUAACCAUGCCAAAGUCAUCUCCUGUAACAAGACUGAUUCCUGAAUGAGAUACACAGGCACAGUUGACAUCAGCUUUCUCAGCAUGUCUGGACCAGAUUCCCAAAACCUCAUCUCCUAGAAUACUAGAGGGAAGGAACAAAAGAAAACUCAUCAUGGCAAGUGCGGGCAGGUUGACUAUAUUCAAAAAGUUUCUUGGCAAUUAAUCUCUAAGUACCCUAUCAUGUUACUUAAAAUACAGGAAGUAAAUUAUGGUAAGUUGUUUGGAGACCUGAAUUUCAUCAGGAUAUCAACUCCUGCCUUUUAAAAAUGACAUUUUAUAAUUUGAAGGGUUUCUAGAUUAAUCUUUUUAAGAUUAAAGUAGUACUUUAUGAAAACUGAUAGAACUAUUUUUUCUUUUUUUUUUUUUGAGACGGAGUUUUCGCUCUUGUUACCCAGGCUGGAGUGCAAUGGCAUGAUCUCGGCUCACCGCAACCUCUGCCUCCUGGGUUCAAGCAAUUCUCCUGCCUCAGCCUCCCGAGUAGCUGGGAUCACAGGCAUGCGCUAACAUGCCCGGCUUAUUUUGUAUUUUUAGUAGAGACAGGGUUUCUCCAUGUUGGUCAGGCUAGUCUCGAACUCCCGACCUCAGGUGAUCACCCCCGCUCGGCCUCCCAAAGUGCUGGGAUUACAGGCUGAGCCACCGCGCCUGACUGAAAACUGAUAGAACUAUUUUUCAAAUUAAAAGUGCUACUUGGCUGGGUCCAGCAGCACAUACCAGUAAUCCCAACAUUUUGGGAGGCUGAGGCAGGAGGACUGCUUGAGGCCAAGAGUUUGAGACCAGCCUGGGCAAUAUUGUGAGAUCCCUAUCUCUACAAAAAUAAAAAUGACUUAUGACAUAGGAAUUAAAAAAAUUUCAGAGAUGGGGUCUUGCUAUGUUGCCCAGGCUGGUAUCAAAACUUCUAGGCUCAAGUGAUCCUCCCACCUCGGCCUGCUACAUCAGAGAUUACAGGCAUGAGCCACUAUAUGCCUGGCUGAUACAGGAAUUUGAUGGCAUUUUUCAUUGGCCAAAAAAAUGGAUAGUCAUGGUUACCUGUCAUACAGCCAGGAAAUUUGAACAAAUUUGGAAGCUUUGACUUCUAAUAGAUUCAAGAUAGCAUUCCUUUAGAUAGAGAAUUAAUAACAGUUGCUUAACAGCACCCAAUACCUUUUUGCCAGUCAUUAAAUUUAGCAUUAAGAAAAAUAUCAGGGUAUCUUUAAAGUUAAAACUUUGAUUUCCUUAAAAAAAAAACUUGAUAAAUCAUGGAAACUGAUAAAACAUGGAAAUAUAUUCAAUAAAAAGGGGUCCCAACAUGAACAUACCAUUUCAAAAUAUGGUAACAAAAACUUGAAACUCAAUUACUAUUCCUUAUUGGAAUGGCUCUAACAGUUCAGAAAUAGGAUUUUCUAACUGGCCUUCAAAGUCAGUUCUUGCCUUGUGAAUAUAUAAGUAUUUACCUAGUCCAUGUAGCCCAAGUAAUUCUGUCAAUAGCGGCAUGAUCCAUAAGAUGUUUUCCUGAAGGCACUUCAUAGACAUGCCGUUUAUAGCAGCCACUAGAGACCUUUUUCAUCAGAUUAAAAUGGGACAAGAAUUCCAUUAGGUGAGAGACAAAAUCCACAGGGGGUUUACAGAAUACUAGCAUAUUGCUACUUGAUUUACAUGUCUAACAUUAUUAAGUAUGCAAAAGAUCACUACAAAAACUUAAUAGGAGAAAAGCUCUGAUAAGUGGGGGAGGAAAGGGGAGCUGUAGGUCAGAAGGUACAAAGGGAGGAGUUGAGAAGCUGGAGCUCUGGAGCUCAGGAACUUUAAAUGCAUUCACUAACACGAAAUGUAAAAGCAGAAGAACUUGCCACCUGGGUAUACAGUAUUGGUACUGUACCUGGAGAUAACUGCUAUCUGCAGAGAAGUCCAUUUGAAUGACAAAGCUUGGAAUGUCUUUGCAGUAGCUGAUUCUGUUAAGAGUGGGGCCCAGCGUUAGGUCAUAAAAAUCCACUGAGUUCUCACUAGAACCUACUGCCAGAUACCGGGAAUCCGGACUAAAUCUGAAUCAAAACAAAACGUAAAAAGUAUUAGACCACAUGAAGUAUUAUAAAUACUUAAGAUCAGUGACUUUUCCUUUCUAGUUCUUAAAAGUAACGUGUGAUAAGGCCUCAAAUAGAUUUACCUGUCAGACACAACUGAUCAUGUAUACUGAGAUUGUCUGGGUUACAUGAAAUAAGGAAGCUUUAUAUUUUACUUAAAUUUUAAAUAUUUCCCCAAUUGUCAUCUCCCAAUUCCUUUAAAAACGUCUAAUGGCUUAAAAAAACUUUCUUAGGCCAGGCCCAGUGGCUCACACCUAUAAUCCCAGAACUUUGGGAAGCGGAGGCGGGCAGAUCACCUGAGGUCGAGAGUUUGAGACCAGCCUGACCAACAUAGAGAAACCCUGUCUCUACUAAAAAUACAAAAUUAGCCAGGCAUGGUGGUGCACGCCUGUAAUCCCAUCUACUCGGGAGGCUGAAGCAGGAGAAUCGCUUGAACCCAGGAGGCACAGGUUGUGGUGAGCUGAGAUUGCACCAUUGCACUUCAGCAUGGGCAACAAGAGCAAAACUCCAACUCAAAACAAAACAAAACAAAAUUUAAUUUUUUAAAUAGAGGCGGGGUCUCACUAUGGUCCCAAACUCCUGGCCUCAAGCAAUCCUUCCCCCUUGGCCUCCCAAGGUACUGGGAUUACAGGUGUGAGCCACAACACCCAGUCAGAACAUCUCAGCUUUUAAAAGCCAUUAGCAUUACAUAAUUAAUAAGCUAACAAUUCAUUAAGAUAGUUUUCUUCCAUCUGGAAAAAACGUUGUCUUAAUAUUAAGCAAAGAACACAGCCCAGCUUAACUAACCUCCAGUUAUUAAGGUGAAAUGACACAACUUGAAUCUUGGAAGAAGAAUUUUUUUUUUUUGAGACGAAGUCUCGCUCUUGUCUCCCAGGCUGGAGUGCGAUGGCGCAACCUCCGCCUCCCGGGUUCAAGCGAUUCUCCUGUUUCAGCCCCCUGAGUAGCUGGGAUUACAGGCGCCUGCCACCACGCCCGGCUGAUUUUUGUAUUUUUAGUUGAGAUGGGGUUUCACUAUGUUGGCCAGGCUGGUCGAGUACUCCUGACUUCAGGUGAUCUGCCUGCCUCGGCCUCCCAAAGUGCUGGGAUUACAGGCAUGAGCCACCGCGCCCGGCCUGAAGAACUUAUUUAAAAGACAAAGUGAAAUGCUAUUUGCCUAGCAAUCUUUGGAGUCAUAUGGGACAAUUCAGUCUCUUGAAAUGGCCCAUGAGUCUUACUGAGGUACGAUAGAGACAUGUAAAAGCUAAGGGAAGCCACUGUUACUAUUUUAUAUAUUGAAGUUCUGAGGAAGGUUUCAUUUGUAAAAGGAUUUUACUGAUGAAAAGUGUACAAGCUUUUGACAGACCUAGAUUCAAUAAUCUUAUCUACUGAUCACACGGAAGUACUCCGUAAAUGGUAGCCACUGUUGAAAAAUGCUUAAGCACUGAAAAACAAAGGUUUAAGAAACAUUUAAAUUAAUUUGGAUUCUGGAACAUUUAAUCAAUAGGUAUUGAUUAAAUUAAUGAACUACAUAUUCCCAAACUGAGGUUACUAAGAGAAGAUAUGUUUGAAAUCACAACUUUAGUUUUCCAGGGUGACAACUUUUGAAGGGCAGAUAGCUCUCUUGUAUUACAGUGGGAGAUACCUCUUGGUGGGAUGAACUUAAUGGACAUGGCUAAGUGUUAACAUGAAUUCAUCAAACAUUACCUACUAGUACUUGCUAUUAUAGUUGGUGCCCAGUGGGUUUAUAAUUUAGCAAGAAGAAUUAAGUAGUAUACAAACAGCCAUAUUUUAGCAUACAAUUUAUAAUACGGGAAAUGCUACAGGCCCUGGGGACCUCUUUUUGAAGGCAAGGCUAUGGAAAAUUUUACAAAUGGAAGUUAAAUCAAGUAUAUACUAGAAACUCUAUUCCAUUUGUUCACUAACCUGAUAUCAUGGAUUGCACAUCUCCUGUCUCUCUUCUUUCCCCAUAUUUUUAGAGAACUCACUAGUAAAAUGAUAAAUUCUCCAUUUUUCAUUCCAAUAGCCACCAUGUCCCCUUCAGGGCUGUAACACACAGUACGAGCAGCAUGUCCCAAAUUCACUUUGUUUAACAUCUUCUGCAUUUAAAAAAAAAAAAAAAAAGAGUCAUAGGAAACAUUAAGUGAAGUACUUCUAAAUUAUACCAGUUUCCCCUCAAAAUGCUCAACAGAAUUCUGGCAGUUCUUUAAGUACUAGCAAUUUAGAACUUCCAACUUUUCUUUUUAGAAGUUGUAACCUCUUUUAAAAAAAUUAUCUGUACUUACUUUAUCAGCAAUAUCCCAAAGUCUCACUGUCCCAUCUUCUGCAGCAGAAAGGAAAAAAUCCCUGGAAGGAUGUGUUGCUAGUCCCCAGAUUGGCCCAUCCACAUGACCGUUAACUAAAAUAUUACAAGCUGCAUUUUUCUCUCCAACUUCGAUUAUUUCAGCAUUCCUUGUCCCAACAAGGAUCUUGCCCUGAAACACAAGCAGGACCAAUACAGUGAAUGUAAUACAACAGCUGCUUUUCUUCUUCAUAAUAUAAAAAUGACCCUAUUGACCUGCUUUCAGAGAACUUUUUGCUUUGAGCUAAUCUAGUAGCAAGGCAGUCAUUAGCUCAUGCAAAUUUUUCUAUGACUACAGGCACACAUCUAUCUGUAAGCACAAUGGGCUAGAUUACAUAUUAGAGUCCAUGCUACAGAAUAGAACUUUUCUGUGGCAGUACACCUGGAUUCUUCAAUAAUCAAAGUUUUUAUUUGAUAAUCUUAGGAUUUCCAAACUGGGGUCAGUGCAGUGGGAUAUAGGAAAAAAUAAUAGAAUUUAUUUUUUAGUUAAAAAGUAAAAGCUUAACUACAAUUUAAUAUGCAGGCUGAAGAUAAUAUCCGUAUGAUUUAUAAAUACACUUAAUAAGUACAAACACGCUCAAAAAUUUUCAUAGGAGUUGUAGUUUUGAAUUUUUAUUUUGAAAUUGACACAUAAUUAUACAUAUCUAUAGGGCAUAGGGUAAUACGCAUAACCAUCACCUCAGACAUUUAUCAUUUCUUUGUGAUGGAAACUUUCAAAAUCCUCUCUUGUAAAUACCUGAAAAUACAUAAAUACGUGAUUCUUAACUAUAGUCAUCCUACAGUACUACAGAAUACUAAAACAUACUAUUCCUAUCUGGCUGUGUAAACUUGUAUCCUUUAACCAGUCCUUCCCUAUCCCCCUCCCCCUCCCCCUUGUCCGCCUCCAGUAACCACUAUUCUACUCUCCACCUCUGUGGGAUCAACUUUUUUAGUUUCUGCACAGGAGUGAGAACAUGUAUUUAUCUUUCUGUGCCUGGCUUAUUUCACUUCACAUCAUGUCCUCCAGUCUCAUCCAUGUUGCCACCAAGAAUGACAGAAUUUCAUUAUUUUUUAUGGCUGAGUAGUAUUUCAUUGUUUGUUUACUGCACGUUUUAUCUAGGGAAUGUGUGUUUUUUUAAAAAAUGGAGACAGCUGUCCUAAUAUGAGUCAACUGCCAAGGGCUUUCAAUUAUGUCUACUAGAGUUGUUAAAUUGGCAGAUUCUAGAAAAUAUUGGAGGUUUACAUACAGUAUUUAGACAGAAUAGCUUCCUAGCUUAUGCACCACACUGGUGCUAACUUUGGCAAAGAAAGCAGCAAAGACAGAGUAAUGUUGGCAAGCAAAUCCAUCGUUAUGCAUUAUUAAGUAUUGUUCAUUAGGCUGCAAAGGGUGAGGGAAUCACAGUAAUAACCACUUUCUGUUUUCUGCUGCACUGUAUCAGCUCAUGGAACAUCUUACUUUGCCUCUGCACACAGAACGAACACAAUCUGUGGCUUGUCCUGUCUCAAGCCUGAAGGCACGGCACCGCCUCAGUUCCUGAUCCCACAGUUUAACCGCUCCUCCUUCUUUUGACCUAAGUAAAUAACCAAGCCAGAGUAAGUGUUCAUUAUUGGCUACUAUAAUUUUUAUUAUAAACAAAUACCAAGUUAUAAGCAGAAUCUUUUUUUUUUAAAAAGGCCCUGAUAUUUAUAAUUUACCUCUAAUAUUCUUGUAAACUUUCUAUGGCAAUUUGAGGAUAUACUAUAUCUCAGUCAAAAUAAACAUCCAGUUUCAGUGAAUUUUAUUUUGAGAAAUACUCUUUUUUUCUGACAUGAGCAUAAUUUUAUUUAGCCUCUACAAUACAUUACAAUACAUUAUCCUCUCUCAUAAUACUUUUUUUUUUUUUUUUAAGAUGUAGUCUCGCUCUGUCUCCCAGGCUUGAGUGCAGUGGCAUGAUCUAGGCUUAUUGCAACCUCUGCCUCCCAGGUUCAAGCGAUUCUCCUACCUCAGCCUCCCGAGUAGCUAGCAUUACAGGUGUGCACCACCACACCCAGCUAAUUUCUGUAUUUUUAGUAGAGAUGGGGUUUCACCAUGUUGGCCAGGCUGGUCUCAAAUACCUUGACCUCAGGUGAUCUGCCUGCCUCGGCCUCCCAAAGUGCUGGGAUUCCAGGUAUGAGCCACUGUGCCUGGCCUCAUAAUACUUCUUGAUUAGGAAGAUGUAAAAAAACAAUUUUAUUAAAAGGAUAAUGGAAAUGUAAGGCAAAAUAAUAGAAUUACAAAUGCUAUGCUACAGAGUUGAUUUAUUUAUUUUUUUGAGACAGAGUGUCGCUCUGUCACCUGGCCUGGAGUGCAGUGGUGUGAUCUCGGCUCACUGCAACCUGUGCCUCCCAGGUUCAAGCGAUUCUUCUCCUUCAGCCUCCCAAGUAGCUGGGAUUACAGGCACCAUGCCUGGCUAAUUUUUGUAUUUUUAGUAGAGAUGGAGUUUCACCAUAUUGGCCAGGCUGAUCCCAAACUCCUGACCUCGUGAUCCGCCCACCUCGGCCUCCCAAAGUGUUGGGAUUACAGGCGUGAGCCACUGCAACUGGCCCAGAGCUUAUUUUUGAAGGCCAAAACAGAAGCAUAUUUAUUCCCUAUCAGGUGUUAAAAUAUCUCACUGGAACAGUUUAGCAGGCUUCUAGUGAGUGGGGGUGUGCAGGAGUAAAUGACGUGGGAAAUACAAGUGUUGGAGGACGAAAUAGAGCCCAUUUAUGGAUUUUAUUCCUGGAAGGGCUGAAAAAUGUAUUCCUUCCUUUUCUGCUAGAUGAAUUGCUUGUCUGAAAGCAUGCCUAUGUGCAUUCUUCCUUUAUGUAAAAGGCACAAAUUCUGCGCUUGUGUUUAAUUAACAUAUGUGGGUUCUUUCAAUCCUGUAUUGAAAUGUACUUCUUAGUCAACUAUAUGUCACAUUUUUUUUUGUUUUUGUUUUUGUUUUUUAAAUGGGGUCUCACUCUGUCACCCAGGCUGGAGUGCAGUGGCACCAUCACAGCUCACUAAAGCCUUGACCUCCCCAGGCUCAAGUGAUCCUCCCACCUCAGCCUCCUGAGUAGCAGGGACUACAGGCAUGUGCCACCACACCCGGCUAAUUGUUGUUUUUUAUAGCGAUGGGGUUUCACCAUGUUGCCCAGGCUGGUCUUGAACUCCUGGGCUCAAGCGAUCCACCUGCCUCAGCCUCCCAAAGUGAUAAGAUUACAGGUGUGAGCCACUGUGCCUGGCCUACAUGUCAUGUUUCAACAUGCAUAUGACUAUGUUGGUGACAAAUCAAAUCAUAAGUAUCUGGUUACUGUUGGGAGAUUUGAAAAUCACUCAGAAGAGACCUCUUCUCAAAUUUUGAGGUCUUGUAUAAAACAGUUUAAAUUUGCCUCAAGCAAAAGGAAACAAGGCAGUUCUCUCUAGUUCCCUCAUCCUUUUCUAAAGCAACAAUGUGCAUUCUACUCCUUAGAAUCCAUUCUGAACAAAAAGAGAGCAGGCAGUCAAAAUACAACCCUGGCUCCAGAUUCCCCCAUGGGCCUCCUACUCAGCAAAUCAUACACAGGCAUACAGACAUUAAGAAAAGUAACUCAACUUGUAGGACAACUACCUAUCCACACCUCAGAAAAAGUAUCACCCCAACAUGAAAAAAAUUGGAAGUGAAUUAAGACCAGAAAUGAGAAUCAAAUAGAAGGCACAUAAAAGGUAAUAAAGGAGAAGCAUAUGAGGAGGAAGGUCGGAGAGGACACUCUGUGUAGCCUAGAAACAACUAGAAUAAUUAACUGCAAACCUCAGGUAGGUCACAAAUGCAUAAAUAUUCUGUGAAAAGAAAGAGGACUCACGGCCUUUCCUUUCCCCCAGUCACGAUAAGUCCAUCUCGCAGGGUGGUGUACAUGGCAAACACAGGCCCGUUGUGAGCUCUCGCCACGAUUCUACACAAUAUGUGAUCUUUCCACACACAGACAUCACCACUGAUGGUACCUGUAAACGUCAAGUUAUUCUGAAAAGGAGUGGGGGAGGGGGAGACAAACUCAUCAAAAGUUCAAAUAGAGUUUAAAUAGAUAAUUUUCUAUGUAUGUGUAAUGCUGUCUCACCCUUGAUACAAAGAGCAUGCAUCGUGUAGUGGCAGCAGCACUGAAUUCACGAGUCAGGAAACCUGAACGGGAGGCUUAGCUUUGUCAGGACCUUUUCCUUUCCAAGUCUGUUGCUUAUUAGCUAGAAUAACCUUAGACAAUUCUUCCCUUCCAAUUCUAACAUACUAUAAUUCUAGGGUUUAUUUUUUAUUUUUUUGAGACGGAGUUUCGCUCUUUGUUGCCCAGGCUGGAGUGCAAUGGUGCGAUCUCAGCUCACCACAACCUCUGCUUCCCAGGUUCAAGUGAUUCUCCUGUCUCAGCCUCCCAAGUAGCUGGGAUUACAAGCGCCAGCCACCACGCCCGGCUAAUUUUUGUAUUUUUAGUAGAGACAGAGUUUCACCUUGUUAGCCAGGCUGGUCUUGAACUCCUGACUUCAGGUGAUCUUCCCGCCUUGGCCUCCCUAAGUGCUGGGAUUAUAGGUGUGAGCCACUGUGCCCGGCCUGAGCCACGGUGCCUGGCCUGGUCUUAUAUUAAGAAUACCCAAAAUGUUCAACUGAAAUUUGACAUGGCACAAACAUUUCAAUAGUCUUUUUCUCAAAAAUGUAAGUGUACUUAAAUAUUCUAAAAUUAUAACUUUUCCUAUAAGUAUUGCAUAAUCACAAAAACAAAAAAUGCACUUAGUUUUUCGAUGCACCAAAGGAUUUAUACAGCCUAGCCAAUGCAGGAUAUUAAAGGAAAGAGAUGUGGAUUGGAAGCCACAGGUCCAGAUGAGAUGGAAUAAAGUGAGAGGAGAGCAGGUCUCCUGAACACCCUUCUGUCAGGGCCAGGAAUUGUGCUAUUUCCUUCUGUCUCACUACCUCCUUCUUCCCUCGAAGUAGAGACACUGGCCCAGAGCACUUCCAGCUGUAUGAUAAGCAGUGUGUUAAAUGAUAAAAAGCAAAGGAAAUCCUAAACCCUAGUACCACCUUAAAUCAUUUGAAAAUCAUGUUUCUUGAUUUACCUUUCUCUCUGACAAAUUUUUAGGACUAUGAAGAACUACUAGGAAGACAGAAAUUUUAGGAUAUUUAGGGUGACAAUUAGAAGAUUAAGGAAGGCUUUUGAGUAUAACAGUAGUCCAAGGAAUCAAAUGUUCAUCAGAAUCCUUAUUAUGGUGGCUCAUGCCUGUAAACCCAGCACUUUGGGAGGUCAAGAUGGGAGGAUCACAUAGCUUAGGAGCUUGAGACCACCUAGGCAACAUAGCGAAACCCUGUCUCUACUAAAAAUGAAAGAAAAAUUAGCCUAGCAUGGUGGUUCCUGCCCUGUAGUCCCAGCUACUAAGGAGGCUGAGGAUCACUUGAACCUGGGAGAUGGAGGCUACAGUGAGCUAUAAUCGCACCAUUGCACCCCAGCCCAGGCGACAGAGUGAGAUACUGUGUCAAAAAAAAAAAAAAAUCCUUUUCCCCCUCUCAUUAACAUUCUUUUCACUCCCUAAUUUCUGAAAGAACUAGAUUUUUGAAAGAUGAAAUAUAUGCUUGACCAGGGCAUGUAAUGAUUAGCAGAUCACAGUAUCAUCUCAACAACAUUCAUGUGGCUGAUGAUCUAAGGCAAGAGAAUGUAAAGUAGUCAAAGUCACACUAUGUGCAUUUUAAGAGACAUACUGCACCAAAUGCAAUAGCGAGCAUGGUCUGCAUCCGGGCAUCUUCCAGUGUGCUCAGUAGCCCUUUUUUGCUAAGAAGAGCUCUUCCUGCCAGGGUCCAGAACUUCACAUGUUUUACUCCCACUGAGACAAACUGGGUAUCUGAAUCUGGUCGGAAUUCUGCCACAAAAAUACGUUGAUUGUGACCAGCUCUGCUGGCAAUUUUGGCACCUGACAAGAUACAACAAAAUUAUCUAGGUUAUUACAAGAACCAAGCUAAUCAACAGCAUCAAACAAAUAUGUAAAAUACAUAGUUCAAAAAACAAAGGCUUAGAAGAGAGGCCAAUGGCCCCUGCUCUACUACCUAGCAAUACAUGAUUUACAAUUAUUUGUGUAUUGAGUCCUUUUCACUUAUCUUCGCUCCAUUAACUUUUCUUUAUAUAACGUAAAUGUUUUGUCUAAAGUGUGGUAGGUAAUAUUAUCCUGCUGAUCUGCCAUUAUCAUUAGAAAUAUACAUAAUUUUCAUAAGAAUCUCCAAAACCAAUCAAAUCAUUAAUAAUAAAUACAUAGUUUCUUGCUGGAAGAAAAUAGCAGUGAAUCAUUUAUAAUGCUAAUAAUGGUUUCAUUAAUUUAUCUGUUUUGUGAGGUUACAGUUCCACUGGGCUUUUAAAGUGAAAUAUACCUACAGUACCACUGUGUACAGUAUAUUGCAUAGGCCUCCACUGAAUGAUUGUUUCAACCACCAACUUUAAGACAAAUAUUAAAUACAGAAUUCCUACUA